AGUGGGAUUAUCUGGACCCAGCUCAGAGAAGCCUGUAUAAAGAUGUCAUGAUGGAGAAUUAUGGAAACCUGGUCUCACUGGGUAAGAAUCUGCUGUUUCUCUAAUUAAAAUAUCUAAGAAGGUAGAGAGAAAUCAGACUAACAGAACAUUUGGACGGAAACCAGUACCAAAACUGCUUUGUUCCAAAGUUCUGAUUCAAACCUUUUAGCCAUUAAUUGUUUCCAUAACUCUCAUCCCUAGCUUCCUUGAGGUGACCAAACUGCAAGCCUUUCGGGCAUCCUGUCUUCAUAAUCUCAUUCCCAUAUUGUUCUGUACUUUCCGUCCUGGCUCAUCCUCCCACAGCUUUCCUCCCACCCCUUUUCACUCUGCGUUCUGGAACCCCUGUUCGUCUUCACAUAAUGUUCCUUCCCUCCUGGCCUUAACUGAAACCUGGCACUAUCCCAAGGACAACGUUUCUCUGGCAGUUUUUCAAGUGGGGGCUGCUUAUUCUCCCACAUCCUCCUCCUUCCCCAUCCUUUGUCUCAAUGUUGGAAGGGGGAAGUUAUUGUUCACUCAGCUUUUAAAUGCUGUCCCCAAAGCAUUAGUUUUCCACCUUCAAACAAAAUCUCUCCUUCUUUGAGGUCUCAGCAGUCUUGCUUUUUCCACUCAAUUCCUUUUCACUAUCUGUCAACUUUUAGUUUGGUCCUUCACACAUAACUUUGUCACAUGUUUCAUAGUCUAUUUUAACUCGUGCCAUGGAUGACCCAGUUAAUACUUCAGCCUCAGUGGAUCUUCAGGGACCCUGCUUUCCACUUUUACUCAGCACCUUACAUCAUUGAUCAUACCAGUUUUGUCAUAACAGGCAAAUCGUAAAUCCCAAUACCCUAUUCUCUGACCAGUUAUUCGGAAAUGGAAGUUUAUUGACUGUGACUAGACGAGGGUAACCAAAACAGACAGGCUUUCUCCCCUUGUGGAGCUUACUACAACUUCUCUAUCUUUCCUACUCCUUUCCACCUAAACCCAUUCAUUAUUAACGAUGUUUCCUGUCCCUUGACGUCUCUGUUUUUUCACUGAGGUGUCCAACCUUUCUGGGCUUGUAUCCCCAUCUAAUCACCAGCAAGCUCUCUUGCUAGCUUGUCAUUAUUCUCUACCCAUUCUGCAAACUUCAAAUCCUGUAUUUGUUAUAAAAUUCACCUUUCUCUCUUUCCUACCCAAAUUGCUAAACAUAGCAGGAGAAAUUCUCUAACCAGAAAGAUUGAUAUCCUUUAUAUAAGUAUGGCCUUUUUCUUCCACUCUCCACUGGGUUUUUAUAUCUUAGCAAUAUUUUUUGUCACUGAUAUGCUCACUGCCCUGUUCUUUUUAGUGACUAUUCCAAAAGCUUAUCCAUCAUUAAGUAGUGAAGCUCACCUUCUGUUUCUCAGAGAAAAUAAAGGCCAAUAAGCAUGAACUCUCAACUUCUCUGCCUCUUAUCUACACACUUAAAGCUGCUCUCAUCUUCUCACCUUUCCAGAAACUAAUCAGUCAUUCUUUUUUCCCUUUUAGUUUCAGUCACUAUUUCUUCUCCCUUGGUACCCUUAUUCUGAUGAUUGGUAUGUUCAUAACUCUUCAACAGGAGAAAAGAGAGGAAAAAAGAAAAAAUCCCUCCUAUGAGUCAGACUCUCCCUCUUGCUGCUGCCUAUGAUUUACUACUUGUUCUCUUCAUAGUCAAGAUUUUGUAAGAGUAGUUAAUGUGUGUUCUGUAUUUCUUUACCUCCCCUUGUGUCUGAGCCCCUUUGUCUUGCCUCUAAUACUCCCUUUAAAUUGUUUAACAGUGAUCUGUAACACGUCAUUGUCAAAUGCAGUAGACUCUUUUGGGACCUUAUUUUAGUCUACCUCUCUAUGAAUAUGUGAAACUCUUUAUUGUUUCCCUCCAUUGGCUUGCAUUCUCAGACUUCCCCUCAGUCUGUACUCUUUCCUUGGGGGACCUUACCUACACUCAGGUCAUCAGCUACCGCUCUGUGAAAAUAAGUCCCAUUUUUUUUUUCAAGUCAUAGCCUCAUUCUGUUGCCCAGGCUGGAGUGCAGUGGUGCAAUCUCAGCUCACUGCAGCCUCCACCUCCUGGGUUCAAGAGAUUCUCCUGCCUCAGCCUCCUGAGUAGCCGAGACAAACAGGCAUGCACCGCCACACCCAGCUAAUUUUUGUAUUUUUAGUAGAGAAGGGGUUUCACUGUGUUGGCCGGGCUGGUCUCGAACUCCCGAUCUCAGGUGAUCCGCCCACCUUGGCCUCCCAAAGUGCUGGGAUUACAGGCGUGAGCCACCGUGCGUGGCCCAAAUCUUUAUUUCCACCUAAGAAAGGUAAUGUGGAGCCUAACUGCCUAGGUUUAAAUCCUUGUUCCACCACUUACUUAGCCUGGUGAGUAUAGUGAUUUAAUCUCUCUUUGCCUCAAUUUAUUUUUUUAUAAAAUGGAAAUAAUAAUAGCACCUACCUCAUAGGGUUAUUGUGAGCAUUGACUGAAUUAAUGUAUGUAAAACACUUGACACACUAACAUGUAGUUAAGAACAAUAUAAAUGUUGACUUAUAUUGUUGUCAUCAUCUUCUCUGUUGAGUUUCCAAUUCCUAGUCAUCUUUUGAAGACCACAUGAGUAAUUCAAACCUGGCAAGUUUCAAUCCAUUAAAAUCAAGGGCCUUCUCUUUCUUUGUUUUACCAGAGCUAAGCACUCCUUUCUUUGUUUUACCUUGUAUAUACUCCUGCUAUUGAAUUUAUCAUACUAUACUACAAUCAUUCUAUAUAUGUUACUUUUCUAACCUCACUGAUUACUGUGAGGAUGGUAGAUAUACCUGUUGCAUUUGAUUUCUCCAGCACUUAGCACAGAGCCAGGCCUAUAUUAUAUGCUUCUUAAAUAUUUAUAUGACUGAGUAAGUACAGUUAACUUAAGACUCAGUAUCUCUUAACUGGAUUAUUACAUUAACCCCUAAACUACCCCCUUGCCACUAGUCUCCUUUUUUAAAAUAUAUUCUCUCUACUGCCACCAAAGUGAUUUUGUAUUAGUUAACUGUGUAAAACUUCUGAUGGUUCCUGAUAGCUUAAAUGAUAAAAAUCUUAAUUUCUUAUCAUAUAGGACCUUCCAAGUAUAGCCUCUGCCUAUCUUUCUUGCCUCACCUGUUUUUUCCUGCACACCACUUUAGUCUUCAGCCAUAUCAGCUGCUGAUAUGUGUGUGUGUGUGUGUGUGUGUGUGUUUUAAUAUACCAUGUUGUCUCUCAGUCACUGCCAGCUUAUCCAUACAUAUGGUAUUCUGGUUGAUAGAACCAAGUAAGUGCCUGGCCCUGCCUUCUCCUAGAACUGCAGCAUGUAAAUACCAUAUGGACAAGGUGUGACAGUGUGCCCACAGAUGAUCUUCUACUUGUAGGCUGUCUUCUUUAUUUCAGCUUAAAUACAGCUUUCCAUAUUCAUCAUUUCUCCUCCCACAGUCUUUUCAUCCUCCUCAAUAAACACUAUCUCCAUCCCUUUGGUGAGAGCUCCCUUGAUGAGAGAUCACUAUUACUCUACUGUUGCAAUGCAGUAUUCUCUUCUACAUCAUCUUAACUGCUUUUCAUAAUGCAACUCUUGUCUAGCUUUAUAGUUUUGGCUUUUCAUUCAUACUUUUCCUUUUCAAGCUUAUUUUUAAAAAAACUUUAAUAGCUACAUCGAUGAUACAGUUGAUAGCUUAAUUUCUCAGAUCUUUGACAUCUUCAAUUUUAAUGACUCUUUCCGCAAUGACUUGCAGAUUGCCACCUUAUUACUGUGUCUUCACAUGGCAGAAGGGGAGAGAGAUAGAGCAAACGUUCUGGUCUUUGUUCCUCUUUUUAUAAGAACACUAAUCCCAUCAUGGGGGCCCAACCUUCAUGACCUCAUCUAAAUUUAAUUACUUCCCAAAGGCCCCGCCUCCAAAUAUCAUCACAUUGUGGAUUAGGGCUUCACCAUAUGAAUAUUUGGUGGGAACACAAACAUUCAGUCUAUAACACUGUCUUAUCUCUUUUUUCUCCUUGACGGUUUAGUCUUUUCUCCUUAUGUUCACAUUCUUCUGUCCUUUUGGCUUCUGGUUUGAUAGGUUACAAUUCUAGCUACCUUCCGAAUAACUAGCGAUUUCAGUUUUAAUUCCAGGUUCUUUGGCGAAACCCACUUUGAGACAACUAUCUGUGUAGAAAAAUUGGCCAUGACCACAGGAUGGGAAGAUAUUGCAUAAGCAUUGCCAAGCCCAGAUCUAAUGGAUAGUCACUUCAAGGCUGCUCUGUGUGGAAGCCUUACUCUUGUUUUUUUCACCUGCCUAUCCUGUUGACCUAUUUAUUUUUAUGUGAAUGUCAUUGUUUUAUUCGCUUUAACAAUAUAUUACAUUUUGUGUCUGGUAAUAUAAGUCAUUCUUUAAUAAUCUUUUUCAGGAUGUACUUCACUAGUCUGCCUUCUUCUAAACUUUAGAUUUAUUUACUUUUUUAUUGGUUCAUGUGAUUUUUGAUUGGAAUGAUUAGUUUCAUAGAUUGAAAGGAAUUGAGAUCCUUAUAAUAUUGAAUCUCUUUAGCCAUUUGGUUGACUCUGUUUAACUGUAUCCUUUUGUCUUUCAGAAAAAUUGUAUGGAAUAUUUUUAUGGAUCUUACACAUUUCUUAUGUUUAUUCCUAGGUUUUAUGUUUUUUGUUACUAUUGUGAAGCAUUUAUAUCAUUUCUGUAUAAUAUUUACUAACUUUUUUUGUACUAAGAACAAGCUUUUUAAUCUUGUUAUGAUUAUAUUUUCAUUUGCUUCUUCCAGGAAUUUUAGGUAUAUAUUCAUAUCAUCUUCAAGUAAUGAUCAUUUUGUCUUAUUCAUUUGAAUGAAAUUGACAGAACAGUAUCCACUAAUCCAACUAACAUAACUGAACAAAUAUUCUGAAGAGACUGCCUUCUCACAAAGAAUUUACAAUCUAGUGGAAGAGACAAAUAACGAACAGUUAAAAAAUGCAGUGUAAUCAUAGCAAUAAUAGAAUUAUGGUCGAGGGCUGGUAAUAAAAAAAUAGAACACCUGAAUCUGUCUAGUGGACUUAGUAAAGGCUUUGUAGAGGAACUGUUGCUUUAAACUUAAAGAUUGCUUUGAAUCUUAAAACCAAAAGUUUGCCAGGUAAACAGUGUUGAGGGACAUUUAGUAAAUGAGAUAUGUGAAGAUAAGACAUGAAAGACUGUAACACAAACAAUUUGCCUACAUAAAGUAUGAUAAAGUAGGUAGGAACAUGACUUGAGGCUUAGAGACUGUGUCAUGAAGAGUUGUAUCAUAGCAAAGAGCUUGAUUCGAUCUUAAAGGUGAUGGGGAGCUGCUAAAUCUACAGGUGAUGACUUGAGUAGAAUUCUGUUUUAUAGAGAUCUCUUCUAGAAUCAGUAAGGCAUAUAUAAUGUGUUGGCAGCCUAAAGACUGGAGCCAAAGAUUAUAAGGCAGCUACAUGAUUGUGAGGGAUGAAAGAUAGGUGCUAGAGAGAAAUCCAGGAUUUGGAUGAUUGAUUAACGUGAGAAGAAGGGAGAAAUACAGGAUGAUUGCUGCUUUGAGACUAUAGGGUAAUGGAUGAUGGUGCCUUUCAAGAGAUAAUUAAAGGUGGGGAAAGGCAUGAAAGCAGAUGAUGAUGACCAUGUUAAUUGUGAGCCCUUUGUGAGGCAUUUAACUGGAGAUAUCUGGAGGGUGUAUAUACAGAACAAGUAAGGAUGUAAAUGUGGGUAACAAUAACAAAAGUCAGUUGACAAAGGAAAAGAAAUAAAUGAGGGAAAUUUAUCAGAAAAGGCCAAAGAAGUAGGGAAGGAAAUAAAAGAAUGUGGUAGUGUAGAAACCAAAAACAGAUAAUGUCAAGAAAUAGGGGUGGUCAACAGUGUUAGAUGCUGCUGAAUAACAUAAGGACUGAAACAUGCCCAUUUUAGGCCAGGCACGGUGGCUCACUUCUGUAAUCCCAGCACUUUGGGAAGCUGAGGUGGGUGGAUCACCUGAGGUCAGAGUUCGAGACCAACAUGGUGCCCCAUCUCUACUAAAAAUGCAAAAAAAUUAGCUAGGCACAGUGGCGGGUGCCUGUAAUCCCAGCUACUUGGGAGGCUGAGGCAGGAGAAUUGCUUGAACCCGCGAGGUGGAGGUUGUAGUGAGCCAAGAUCACUCCAGCCUGGGCAAUAAGAGUGAAACUCUGUCUCAAAAAAAAAAAAAAAAUGCCCGUUUUAUUUUUAUUUGAGUCAUUGGUAAUCUAAUGAGAAGUUUCUCUAGAUGCUGGAAACAGAAACCAGAUUUCGCCACAGGUUGCAGAAUAGAUUGAAUAGGAAGAGGUUGGGCUUGGAAAACAUAAGAAAUAGAAAACCUCGGUGUUAAGAUUUUUUUUCAAUGCUUGGCUUUCAUAAAGAGAAGGAUUUCAGGUUCAAGAUAAAAUUGGACAUAUUUAUGUAAUGGUAGGAAAGUGUCAAUAGAGAGUGUGUAUUGAAGAAAGAGGAAAGACGGGAUAAUUAAGCAAAUGCCCAGAGGUGAGUAGGAUCGGUAAGUGAUGGAUGGAUUAGCCUUGCAUAAGAAUCAGAUAUAUCUUUAUGUACCAUUGGCAGAUAAUUUUAUAGGUAGAGGACAGAAAGUUGAGGGAGUUCUUUCAUGUUUUUUCAUUAUGUGAAAGAAAAUACAGCCCACUGAAAAAUUUGAGAGGGGACACUAAAAAGCCUUAGAAGAAAUAAAAUUUCUAGUAGUUUCUUAGGGGAAUAGGAAAAGGUUAUUUUAGAAUAAAAUAAUGAAGUAAGCAAAUAGAAAAUUCAAAGAUGACUCCACAAAAAAUUGAGAGAAAAGAGGAUGUAUGAAAAAGGAGCUUGUUUAGGGCCAAAUAUAAAUGUGGUCAUUAUUGAAUCUUCUAGCGGAAUUAUCUAAUAUCUAUUCCAGCAAGAGAUGGAAAAUCAGGAAGAUGUCCGAAGCGGGCCUAGAUGUACUAUAUGACACUCUGUUAUAUCAUAGACCACUGUGCUGUCUUUUCUUCAACACAUGCAAGAUUUUCAUUUCUCAGAUGUCAUGCAGCCUCUCAGUUGGAACAAGAUGGUGAACCUUGGGUCUUAUAUUGUUAGAGGGUUUAGAAUCACAUGUACUUGAGGUAUGAUUUGUGGUAGGUAAAGUCAUAAGCUACCACAGACUGCCCUUUUUGGUUGUUGCUCCCAUGAACUCUGACCAUGUUUCUUAAUACUUAUUUUAUUCUGCAUCUCGAUAUCAUAGACUCUCUGUCACCUAACCCUUUAUUAUUGUUUUUAAAAGCCAUUUUGUCUCUUUAUACAGGAGCUGCUUUUUACUUAAUAUUUUCUUUAUCAUAUUAUUUUCUUUCCCCAUUUUUUACUUAACAUCCAUUCCAUUUGGCAGGGGGGCUUCAUGUCUUAUCUCUGAAUCCUGGCUGAUUACAAUGUUUCUGGAGUGCUUUUGAUGGGCAAUGUUUUGAACAGAGAUAAGGAUGAGGAGCCAACUGUAAAACAAGAGAUUGAAGAAAUUGAGGAAGAAGUGGAACCACAGGGUGUAAUAGUUACAAGAAUCAAAAGUGAAAUUGACCAGGAUCCUAUGGGUAGAGAAACAUUUGAACUUGUUGGUAGGUUAGAUAAACAAAGAGGGAUCUUCCUAUGGGAAAUACCAAGGGAAUCUUUGACCCAGGAACAGAGAAUGUUCAGAGAAAACACUAACAUUAUCCGUAAAAGACCAAACUCAGAAGAGAAAUGCCAUAAAUGUGAAGAAUGUGGAAAGGGUUUUGUCCGCAAGGCCCAUUUCAUUCAACAUCAAAGGGUCCAUACUGGUGAGAAACCUUUUCAGUGCAAUGAAUGUGGGAAAAGUUUUAGUCGCAGUUCAUUUGUUAUUGAACAUCAGAGAAUUCACACUGGGGAAAGGCCCUAUGAGUGUAAUUACUGUGGAAAAACCUUUAGUGUGAGCUCAACCCUUAUUAGACAUCAGAGAAUCCACACUGGAGAAAGACCCUAUCAGUGUAAUCAGUGUAAACAGAGCUUCAGCCAGAGAAGGAGCCUUGUUAAACAUCAAAGGAUUCAUACAGGUGAGAAACCCCAUAAAUGUAGUGACUGUGGGAAAGCCUUCAGUUGGAAAUCACACCUUAUUGAGCAUCAAAGAACUCACACUGGUGAGAAACCUUAUCACUGUACCAAAUGUAAGAAGAGCUUUAGUCGAAAUUCAUUGCUUGUUGAGCAUCAAAGAAUUCACACUGGGGAAAGACCCCAUAAAUGUGGUGAAUGUGGGAAAGCCUUUCGAUUAAGCACAUACCUUAUACAACACCAAAAAAUUCACACUGGCGAGAAGCCUUUUCUUUGUAUUGAGUGUGGAAAAAGUUUCAGUCGGAGCUCAUUCCUUAUUGAACAUCAGAGGAUCCAUACUGGUGAAAGACCUUAUCAGUGCAAAGAGUGUGGGAAAAGUUUCAGUCAGCUUUGCAACCUUACUCGUCAUCAGAGAAUUCACACAGGAGACAAGCCCCAUAAAUGUGAGGAAUGUGGAAAAGCCUUUAGUAGAAGCUCAGGUCUUAUUCAGCAUCAGAGAAUUCACACCAGGGAGAAGACUUAUCCAUACAAUGAAACUAAGGAAAGUUUUGAUCCAAAUUGCAGUCUUGUUAUACAGCAGGAAGUCUACCCUAAGGAGAAAUCUUAUAAAUGUGAUGAAUGUGGGAAAACUUUUAGUGUUAGUGCUCAUCUUGUACAACAUCAAAGAAUCCACACUGGUGAAAAGCCCUAUCUAUGUACUGUCUGUGGGAAAAGCUUCAGCCGGAGCUCAUUUCUUAUUGAACAUCAGAGAAUCCACACUGGUGAGAGACCCUAUCUGUGCAGACAGUGUGGAAAAAGCUUUAGUCAGCUUUGUAAUCUUAUUCGACAUCAGGGUGUUCACACAGGUAAUAAACCCCAUAAAUGUGAUGAAUGUGGAAAGGCCUUUAGCCGGAACUCGGGUCUUAUUCAGCAUCAGAGAAUACACACAGGAGAGAAACCUUAUAAGUGUGAGAAGUGCGACAAAAGUUUCAGUCAACAGCGCAGUCUUGUCAACCAUCAGAAGAUCCAUGCAGAGGUGAAAACCCAAGAAACCCAUGAAUGUGACGCUUGUGGUGAAGCCUUUAAUUGCCGUAUUUCUCUUAUUCAGCAUCAGAAAUUGCACACAGCAUGGAUGCAAUAAAUGUAGAGCAAUACAUAAGCUCAAUUUGAUUUGAGACUAGUACCCAAGUGCAGUUUUAGUAUGGCUCAACAUGGGUCAGAUUUAGUGAUAAAGCAAAUUCUCCUUGGCCUCAGGCAAAUAGUUUCUAAAGAUUCUGUGAAUAGUGGACAACUGCCCAUGAGCAUUUGACUUCCCUUACUCUUUGAUGAUCGUAGAGAAAGACUUGGUAAUUUAUCUAAGUAUCUUUAAUAAAUCUUUCAGCAGAGAGAUUAAACCUAGGUUCAGAGCAUGGGUGCUCUGAGGGACAAAGUUGGAUUAGUAUAAGGGAGCUGGAGCAGCUGAUAGUGGAAAACAGAAUAAUGAUUCAAAGAGUCUUCUGUCACCAUGUCAUAUUGUGGUUCUUUCAGUUCCAUGAUAUGUUUGGCUCUGCAUGCCAAAGUCCAGUGAUUAAGCAUAUAUAAGUUGUCAAGGAAACAAAGCCCAAAUGUUUUUAAAACAAGUAUACAGUUUUUGUCAUUGUUUAAGAAAGCCAGUUGUUUGGCAUGUGAGUUAAAGGCAGUUCCAAUGCCUGAUGGUUCCCAGAUCUAUGAAAUGAGUGGACCAUUAACCUUACAUGUAAAGAUUAUGUUAGUAAUUAAGAAACCUAACAAAGGUGUUACCAAGGAACCUUUGGGAGUGCCUUUUUUGUUUUUCAAGAUGGACCCAAAAAAGUGGAGGAAGAUAUUGUUCUUUUGUGCCCUCCUACCUGUGAGAGAUAUUUGUAGUCCUAUGUGAAUGAGCUUAUCCCUCCACAACCAGGUGCAUAUGAAAGUGUACAUAUUAUGACUGCCAAGUAUUGGAAAUGAAAAGACCUGGAGUCUAUGCUAGGAAGCUGAGAUAUUUUGGUAUUGCAUUGGUUUUUAUGGUAACUAGGUUUUGCAUGCAAUUAAAAAUCCUUAUUUCUUGUUCUAGGGCUUCCCUUAGUUAAUGGUUAUUAUAAACCUAUUAAUUCAUCUGUUUUAACCAUUAAAACCUGUUUUGUUUUUA